GGAAGGAACAGAGAGCGGCCGGCGCGUCCUCCUCUCUGGGUAAAGCCGCGUUGGUUCCUGCCGCAGCGCUGUGCUUCGGACUCCUAGGGGGCCUCUGGCCGUUUGAAUGAAUCGACAAUAUCAGAGUAUUGUGGACACUUUUUAAUGGGGCCGGGGAGGGGCCGCCGCUGCCGAGAACUGAGGGCGACAGAACAAUCCCACCUCUUGUGAGGAGCAGGUCUGCCAUUCUGCUUGUCAGUUCUCACCUUCCCCUCCUCCACGGCAAAGAGUCCCUUUCACACCCUUCUGAGUGUGCGGGUGCGCCCAGUUUUACAAGUCCUCUGUCCUGCCAGGGUAGUGGGAGAAGCACGCGAUGGGGCUAGCGCCCAGUCCUGCGGGGGCAGGCGCCAAGCUCCCGGGAGUCCGCAAGUCGCUUCCUAUAUUGGCAAGCUUCAAAUGAGACAUUAGAAUCUCCGGCAACCUUCCUUCAAACCUGAACCGGGGAAGAGAAUAAGCCGCCCUAUGGCCAAGGCGCAAUUGCGUACCCGUGUGUACAGGUCCAUGCCCUGUCCCCUACACUCUAAUUUUCUCAAAGAAAAUUGUUUUGCCAAAAGUAACCCUGAGAAAUGCAGACGCUCCAAACGCCCUCUCCACUUCGGAUGAAGCCAGCAUCUAGUAGGGUCUCCGGCCCUCAAGAAGCCAUGCUCUUUCACGGGAUCUCCGGAGGCCACAUCCAAGGCAUCAUGGAGGAGAUGGAGCGCAGAUCCAAGACUGAGGCCCGUCUGGCCAAAGGCGCCCAGCUCAACGGCCGCGACGCGGGCAUGCCCCCGCUCAGCCCGGAGAAGCCCGCCCUGUGCGCCGGCUGCGGGGGCAAGAUCUCGGACAGGUACUAUCUGCUGGCUGUGGACAAACAGUGGCAUCUGAGAUGCCUGAAGUGCUGUGAAUGUAAGCUGGCCCUCGAGUCCGAGCUCACCUGCUUUGCCAAGGACGGUAGCAUUUACUGCAAGGAGGAUUACUACAGAAGGUUCUCUGUGCAGAGAUGUGCCCGCUGCCACCUUGGCAUUUCCGCCUCGGAGAUGGUCAUGCGCGCCCGAGACUCUGUCUACCACCUGAGCUGCUUCACCUGCUCCACUUGCAACAAGACUCUGACCACGGGCGACCAUUUCGGCAUGAAGGACAGCCUGGUGUACUGCCGCGCCCACUUCGAGACCCUCUUGCAAGGAGAGUAUCCACCGCAGCUGAGCUACACGGAGCUGGCGGCCAAGAGCGGCGGCCUGGCCCUGCCUUACUUCAACGGUACGGGCACCGUGCAGAAAGGGCGGCCCCGGAAGCGGAAGAGCCCAGCGCUGGGAGUGGACAUCGUCAAUUACAACUCAGGUUGUAAUGAGAAUGAGGCAGACCACUUGGACCGGGACCAGCAGCCUUAUCCACCCUCGCAGAAGACCAAGCGCAUGCGAACCUCUUUCAAGCAUCACCAGCUCCGGACCAUGAAAUCCUACUUUGCCAUCAACCACAACCCGGAUGCCAAGGACCUCAAGCAGCUUGCCCAGAAAACAGGUCUGACCAAAAGAGUUUUGCAGGUUUGGUUCCAAAACGCACGAGCCAAAUUCAGAAGGAACCUUUUGCGGCAGGAGAAUGGGGGUGUUGAUAAAGCUGACGGCACGUCGCUUCCGGCCCCGCCCUCAGCAGACAGCGGAGCUCUCACUCCACCCGGCACUGCGACCACUUUAACAGACCUGACCAAUCCCACUAUCACUGUAGUGACAUCCGUGACCUCUAACAUGGACAGCCACGAAUCCGGAAGCCCCUCACAAACUACCUUAACAAACCUUUUCUAACAUUGGUUUUUUUUUUUUAGUUUUUAAAUUCUUCCUCUUCUUUUUAUUAUUAUUCUAAUUAUUAUUAUUUUAUUAUUUACAAGACUUUUUUUUUCUUCUAACCCACAAGAUAUUUGGGGAAUAAAAAUAACAGCUUGGUGUGUAGCAUCUGCAGCCACUUGGCAAAUGAGUUUACAGUAUUGUCUCCUUUAAGUGAAUAUAUUUUGUCUACAAAGUGUAUUUGGAUUUAAAAAAAUUAAUUAGGUCUUUCAGUUGGUAAGGAGAGUUUUUGAAUAAUUCUAAUAAGUGCCUCUUAAAAUUGUAUGUUACUUAUUUCCAGAAUCUCGAAGAAAAAAGAAAAAAGAGUGGUAUUAUUAUGGGCAAAUAAUCAUAUUCCCACUUAAAUGAUUAGGUUAAUAAAGAACCAGAUAAUUAAUUAGUUACUUUUUAAAUCUUGCAAUUGUAUGUGUGAUUAUGGAGUUUUGAAAACGUUACAUUUUUUAAAUCUUAAAACUGAAAACUUGUUUUUAGUAUUUCUAUUUCUUACCUGAACUGUUAAUUCAAGUGAGGAAUAUGAUGAAAUAAAAGCAUUAACUACAGACAUUUUAAAUAGUAAUGAUUAAUUAGGUGAGAAAUCUAUUACAGGAAUGUGACUUUUCCUUCUCUUAGGGGUGUACAACUCUAAAAACUUUUUACUUGGUUAUUUGUUUUUCAACAUUUGAAAAAUACUUAAGCUCCCUAUGUAUCCAUGAAAAUUCCGCAUUGAUUUUGACAUUCCAUACUUUUAACCUCCUAAAGCUAAAAACAAUAGCUCGGAAACCAUUCUUUCUAGUUACUUUUUUUCCCAGGGAAAAUGGAAAUAAGCAAAAUAUAAUGUUUUAAGAAGUAAAAAAAUCAAUAUAAUUUAAUUAAUAGCUCUAUUAAUUGGCUUCAGCUGUACCAUGAUAUUGUAUCUGGCAUUCUAUAUGAAUAAUGUUUAAAAUACCCAGCCUGGUAGACUUAUACCAACAAUUGGUUUUGUUUUGUUUUAUUUUAUUUUGACAUAGGUUGACUUAUGUAUUGAAAAUAAUUUUUCUGAUAUUAGAGAUUUGAAGUUAUUAGUCUUAAAGUAGAUAAACUCAGAAGCCUUGUGGAUGCUGAUCUGAAUAUAUUUCCUAGUUUACAGUAGCAUUUUUUUCUUUUAAUUUAAGCUAAAAUCUUAAUGGUCUGGGCAGUGGUGAAUGUUCAUCUAUUACGCUUCUGUUGUAGUUAAAUACCAAUUAGAUUGUGGAUUUCCUAAAAAAAUAAAAAAGAAGUCAAGAUAUAUGUCUUGCUUUAGUGGAUUGUUAAGAAUAACUUUGCACAUAUUUUCCACUUUUUGGACCCCUUAAAUCUCCUUUGGUGGUCGAAGUGGCUAUUUAAUAGAUUUUAAAGGUGUCCUUCUGGCUGUAUAAAUGUGUGGUUACAUAUUGACAGUUCACUGCCCACAUUAAAGUGCAUUAUUGUAACUUUUGCUCAGGGUCUUUAGAAAAUUAGCACAGAAAGUAGCUUAUUUUUUAAAAAAAGAUGAUGGAAGAUAAGUUAACACUGUAACAGAAGAAAGGUGUGAUUGCCAUUAUAUAUUUAGCAAGUAUGGUUAUCAUCUUAUAUGGAGCUUAAAUCUUGACUUUUCAUACUUCUAUUACAUUUUGGGCAUUUACCACUAACCAGACCAAACAACCUUGGUAAGGCUGAGAUCUUAUUAAUACACUUUUACAGGUAAAAUAUUGACACUUAUAAAUUUUGUUCUUUGACAGAACAAUAUAUGGUACUAUAUAGAUCUACUUUAUUAAGUAGACUAAUUAUAACUCAGUUCUCCUAUGUGCCUUAUGAUAUAACUUGGAAGUAAGUUUGUGAAAAAUCAGGAUAUAUGUGUUGUUUGUUAAAUUAACUGUUUUAAGCCCUUUUAACACCUCACUAGUUUUGUACUGUUUUACCUCUUAUUUCUGAAACUCUUUUUAUGGUGUAUCCUGUUAGAGGGGACAAACAUGUCAUAGAAAGCAGUUGUGCACUCUUUCAAAUAUAGUUGAUAAAUUCAAUAAUCUUAUAUAUUGAGCUUCGUGUUUAUAGUACAGUAAGUGGUCUAGCAAAAUUGUCCAUGUUUCUUUGUUUAUUGAUAAAUGCAUUGUAUAGAAACUAUUUCCCCUAAAUAUUUAUGGACCAAACAAUUGUGAUAUAUCCUAUUAAAUUUGUGUGAAUAAAACAUUUUGAAUCUAAGGAGUUUUCUUUCCCAUCAGUUUUAUUUAAGUUUUAACCGUACUAGUGUGUUCCAGCAUCUAUAUGUAAAAGCUUUUCAAAUGGUAAUACAACAUUGUUAGAAAUAUUUAAACAUACAAAUAGUUUUUAGACUUCCAAACUUCUGAUUCAUAUGAAAUGUUACACAUUGUUGCACAGGCAGUGUAAUUCAACCUAGAAAUACCUUUGAAUAUAUUUGCUUAUAACAAAAGUAAUGCCCCACUGAUUUGACUCAGUCCAAUUUUUAGAAUAAAAAGGCUAAUUAGCAUAUAAAGUAAUUGCAUGGAACGAAACCUUAAAUAUGAUUAAGAUUUCAUGUUAGGUCUAUUGAGCACAAAUGGAUAUUUGUAAAUCUAAAUAGAAAUUGCAGACCCCUAAAAGCCAAGUUGCUCUGUAGUUAAUAAAUUGUCACUAUGAUUUUUUUCAGGGAGAACAAAUCUUGGGGCAUUACAGCCAAACAUCCCGACGUUUGAAAAUUCCCUAAAGUAUUAAAAGAAGGGGAAAAGUUUGAUCGGAAAUCCACUGCAGUGAAGACAAAGACACUAUUAGGUUAUGAUAAUCAUACAUUAAAAAAUUUAUUAAGCCAAAAAAAAAGAGAGAGAGAGAGACUUAAAUGUCAUUUACUGAAUGUUAACGAAACUUGUGUUCUUUAUGGUGUCUAACACAACUGAAGGCCUAAAAUUAUGUGGUUUAAACAAAAUUAGAUAAACCAUGUACAAAACCAGAGCAACCUGGCAGUAAUAUGCCCACCCCAUAUUUGAAAAAAAUUAUUAUUGAAAAAAAUUUCACACAUUUGUCAAGCACAGUUGUAAAAUAAAGUCCAAAACAUUCAUUUCACCUGCUUGCUAAUGUGUAUUAGUCCUGUUAAUGGCAUUUUCCAACUGUAAAUUCAAAGAAAAGCUAUCACCCAUUUAAGAGUAUAGGGAUCAAACCCCAGUAAUUUUAGCAUUAUUGUUUAUCACUUCCUUUUUAAACAGAAAUCUCUGCAUGCACUUUUACAUAUGUCACCUCUAGUGUACACCUCUGUAUGAUGACUUAUCUUUGCUGUUUCUUGUAUGAUAAAUAGCUUUCAUUAAUAAACAUUUAUUUGAUGCAAACAUAGUUAACUUUAUGUUAAACACAUGCUGUUGAAAUUAAUUUUGAACACUUAAAGAGGCAGCACAGUACAUUUACAACUUGUUAUACUAAUGAAAAAAUACAAACAGCAUAGUGAGAUUAAAUUCUGGUAAUCUAGGAUAAAAUUACUUACUUGGUUUUUACCUUUUCAUGACUUAUUUUCAUUUGUUGUAUUCAAUUGCCACAUGUAUUAAAAAUAAAAAACAAAGUGAACCCAAAUUACAACAAAAUAAACCUUAGAAUAAACUAUUGUGUAAAAUUUCAGCAACUUUUUUAGAUUACUAGGGUAAAAUUUAUAGAUCCUAUGUGAGUUUACAUGUUUGCUAUGCAAUGAACAAAUUUAUUGAUGUAUACAAAUAUAUUCUGAACUAUAAAAAGAUCCAAUCUUUGCAUAGUUCAAUUACAUAUGAUUAUUACAAACAAAAAAGCAAAUGGAAAGACAGACAAAUAUUUAGGAAUGAGGUUUUUUUUAAUUGUUAAAGGGAAUAUUUGAAGAAUAAAAUUUUAGCUAUUCCUAUUUAGCCGUAUAUCCAAAGCAUAUGUUAAACAAACUAACAUAUACUUUCCAGAAAAUUUUUCAUUAUGAUGAAAUUUUUAUUAUAUACAAAUGAACCCUAUGUAAAUGAUGUAACUUUUAUGAAUGACAGACAUUAAAUAUUUCACUUACAUGUAUUCUCAGAAUUUUGAAUGUUUUCUUAAAUGCUUUCACUUCCUGAAUAAUAAAAAGAAAAAAUUUUAAAGAAGAGAGAGCAACUUACUAAUAAAAAAAAGCAAUGCACCAUGACAAGUAGACUAUUUUGAGUGAUCACAAAUCAUGCUGGUUUUGUCAGUAACUUGAAUGUUUAUGCCUCAUUGAAACCUCAUCCACAGCUAUAGCAACUUAAAUAGAUUUUCCAAUGCAUUUCCAGCCAGUUUAUUCAAAUCUUUGCCCUACAGUCUUGCCUUCUUUCCCUGUUCUGUCACCUGUGGCAAUUUCAUUUAGAAGUAUUUUGGAACUUCGCCUGGUUUUACAGACCUUUAAAUAUUUGUCUGGUAUGUGAAAUGCAGGAAGAGACCAGAGAGGGAAAGAACAUAACUGAAAUUAGACAUCUGAAAAAAAAAUACAAAUUUGAAACAGGCACAUUUUUUAAAACCAAAAAAAAAAAAAAAAAGAGAGAGAGAGAGAAAGGAGUACUAAUUAUGUGAGUGGGAAGAGGAAGCGUGUGAUGCAGAGCUGGAAGGUCUGUUGUGCUUUACUGUGAUGUAAAGCAGUCUUUGAGUCUGGGCAACUGCACAUUUACUGUUUGGUGUGGAAUAGAAAAAUGUGGACCUCUUAGUUGAGAGCAGGACACUAAAUUUUCAUAGCUUCUACCUCCCAGUUGCCUGGGUUAGUCUAACUUCUGGCAGAUUGAUCUUGGGCAAAAAGCUUCACUGAGAGUUAGUGUCUGUGUGCUUUGGUUGAAUAGCCACCUUAAUACUGACUUACAUAGUGGGUAGGUUUUUGAUACCUCAAAUAAGGAUAAAACUCCAUAAUAAAGGACCCAAAGCAAAUACUUUUAAAACUUAGGUGAUUUUUCAUCACCUAAAACAUAAAUAGCUUUAUUUAGCAAAAUCCCAGUGGAAUCUACCACACAUUCUUUUAUAAUAACCCUUUUUUGGGAGUCAAAGUAUUGUUUUUUUAUUAGCCACAUAUAAAUAUCAUCUCAUUUUCUGUUGCAGUGUGACUGCAAGGCAUGUUGUGGUGGAAAUCAUUAGAACUGGGAAGCUCUGGAAUGGAAAUUUGGAAUCGUGUCAUUCUAGGCUCUUAAAGAGAAUAUUAGGGAUAAUACUGUUGUAAAAAAUAAAUAUAAACACCUAAUUUUGUAUGAAGUUUUGCUAUUUAAAUUUUAACUAUGUUAUAAACAAAGCUAGCUUUACUUGUAGAGAGUUCGUGUACUCUUGAGCUCAUUCAAUAGCUUUUACAUUUUGUAGUCUCUUCCACAACAGGGCAAAAUAAGCACAGUAGGACUUAGUCCAAAUUGACGAAAUAUCAUUGAAUUUUCUUUGAAAGCAUAUAUAUAGAUAAACUCUGGAUUGGUCUUUUAGAUCUGUUUUCUGUUUUUAGUAAUUGGGAACAAACUCUUGAUAUUAAAAUAAAUAAAAUGCCUCUAAUGUAAAGCCACAGCCCUGCUUCUAGCCAAUGUCAAAAAUAGGAAGUUUUUUUAAUGGUUUACUGUUGAUUUUAAACAUUUUAAUAAUAGUGCUCUGCCCUCACAACAGUUUUUUUUUCAGAAUAAUAUUAUGAUUUACCUUAUUUUAAAAAUAAAUUAUAAUUCUAACUUAAAAUAUUAUUUUAAAUGCCCCUCUGGGAAGAUUUCCGUUUUAUUUUAUGAGGUUCCCUGGCAGUUGGGGGGGUGGUGAGGUUGGGAGAGGGAAAGUUUAGAACUGUGCAUGAUACUCAAGGAAAAGUCUAUGAAUAUGAUGUAAGUAGUAACAUUAUUGCCACAACUAAAUUUCUGUUUAACUGUGUUGCAGAAUAUGAUAAUGUCAUCUAACAUCACUCCCUACUUGCAACAUUCCUCUGUGAAUAUUAAUAUAGUUAACCCUCCCUUAUUAUGUAUCAUAUCAAUAAGUUUCUCUUCCCUUGGAUUAAUUUUUGCUUCUUUGCAUUACAUUUUAUCUUGUGCUAAGAUAACAAAAAGCAAGCAAGAAUAAAGAUCCAGAUAUUAGCCAUAUGUAGAAAGUUCCUGGUGUGCAUUUCUGUGUACUUUUCCCUCACAUAUUAGAAUUGUCAGGAAAGUUUUUUUCUUUUGGAACUUUCUGUUUACAUUUUGCAUGAUCUUAUAAAUUAACCUGAAGAGUAAUUGGAUACCUUUUAUGGUUAUUUGAAAAUAAAAUUUGCUACAAAUAAGA